AGUGUUGCAACUGGGCCUGGCAUGUUUCAGUGUGGUGUCCAGCAGUGUCUCCCACUCCUUGUGAAGUCUGAGGUUGCAAAAGGACUGUGAUCAUAUGAAGAUCAUCCAGGAGUACAACUCGAAAUUCUCAGAAAACAGGACCUUGAUGUGAGAGGAGCAGGUUCAGGUAAACAAAGGGCGAGGACCCGAGCGAGCUUAAGGAGUGGGGUGCAGCGUCUGGUCAGCGGAGGGUGAAUUCUCAGGACUGGUCGGGAGUCAAGGUGCCACAUCUCCUGCCUUUCUGCUCACUUUCCUGCCUGUUUUGCCUGACCACAGCCAUCAUGCCUCGGGGUCAGAAGAGUAAGCUCCGUGCUCGUGAGAAACGCCGCAAGGCGCGAGAGGAGACCCAGGGUCUCAAGGUUGCUCACGCCACUGCAGCAGAGAAAGAGGAGUGCCCCUCCUCCUCUCCUGUUUUAGGGGAUACUCCCACAAGCUCCCCUGCUGCUGGCAUUCCCCAGAAGCCUCAGGGAGCUCCACCCACCACCACUGCUGCUGCAGCUGUGUCAUGUACCGAAUCUGACGAAGGUGCCAAAUGCCAAGGUGAGGAAAAUGCAAGUUUCUCCCAGGCCACAACAUCCACUGAGAGCUCAGUCAAAGAUCCUGUAGCCUGGGAGGCAGGAAUGCUGAUGCACUUCAUUCUACGUAAGUAUAAAAUGAGAGAGCCCAUUAUGAAGGCAGAUAUGCUGAAGGUUGUUGAUGAAAAGUACAAGGAUCACUUCACUGAGAUCCUCAAUGGAGCCUCUCGCCGCUUGGAGCUCGUCUUUGGCCUUGAUUUGAAGGAAGACAACCCUAGUGGCCACACCUACACCCUCGUCAGUAAGCUAAACCUCACCAAUGAUGGAAACCUGAGCAAUGAUUGGGACUUUCCCAGGAAUGGGCUUCUGAUGCCUCUCCUGGGUGUGAUCUUCUUAAAGGGCAACUCUGCCACCGAGGAAGAGAUCUGGAAAUUCAUGAAUGUGUUGGGAGCCUAUGAUGGAGAGGAGCACUUAAUCUAUGGGGAACCCCGUAAGUUCAUCACCCAAGAUCUGGUGCAGGAAAAAUAUCUGAAGUACGAGCAGGUGCCCAACAGUGAUCCCCCACGCUAUCAAUUCCUAUGGGGUCCGAGAGCCUAUGCUGAAACCACCAAGAUGAAAGUCCUCGAGUUUUUGGCCAAGAUGAAUGGUGCCACUCCCCGUGACUUCCCAUCCCAUUAUGAAGAGGCUUUGAGAGAUGAGGAAGAGAGAGCCCAAGUCCGAUCCAGUGUUAGAGCCAGGCGUCGCACUACUGCCACGACUUUUAGAGCGCGUUCUAGAGCCCCAUUCAGCAGGUCCUCCCACCCCAUGUGAGAACUCAGGCAGAUUGUUCACUUUGUUUUUGUGGCAAGAUGCCAACCUUUUGAAGUAGUGAGCAGCCAAGAUAUGGCUAGAGAGAUCAUCAUAUAUAUCUCCUUUGUGUUCCUGUUAAACAUUAGUAUCUUUCAAGUGUUUUUCUUUUAAUAGAAUGUUUAUUUAGAGUUGGGAUCUAUGUCUAUGAGCGACAUGGAUCACACAUUUAUUGGUGCUGCCAGCUUUAAGCAUAUGAGUUUUGAUAUUCUAUAUUUUUCAAAUCCUUGAAUCUUUUUUGGGUUGAAGAAGAAGAAAGCAUAGCUUUAGAAUAGAGAUUUUCUCAGAAAUGUGUGAAAGAACCUCACACAACAUAAUUGGAGUCUUAAAAUAGAGGAAGAGUAAGCAAAGCAUGUCAAGUUUUUGUUUUCUGCAUUCAGUUUUGUUUUUGUAAAAUCCAAAGAUACAUACCUGGUUGUUUUUAGCCUUUUCAAGAAUGCAGAUAAAAUAAAUAGUAAUAAAUUAUA